AGGUGGUUCAUGUACUCUGGCGGGGAAGGAGAAGUCAGGCGCUCCGGGCUCGCCCGCUAGGUCGGGGCCGCGGCGUCCCCCACCCUAAGUCCCACCUCCGGCCGGGCAUGGGUACCCGGGCGGGCCUGCCUCGGCCUGGGCCCACUCACUGGUCCAGAAGCAGCUGUAGGUGCCCACCAAGCCCAUGACGACGCUGCUGGCCAGGGUCCAGGAGUCUCGCUCUGUCGCCAGACUGGAGUGCAGUGGCACAAUCUCGGCUCACUGCAACCUCCGCCUCCCGGGUUCAAGCUAUUCUCCUGCCUCAGCCUCCUGAGUAGCUGGGACUACAGGCGCAGGUCGCCACGCCCGGCUAAUUUUUUUUUUUUUUUGUAUUUUAGUAGAGAUGGGGUUUCACCAUGUUGCCCAGGUUGGUCUCGAACUCCUGAGCUCAGGCAGUCCACCCACCUCAGCCUCCCAAAGUGCUAGGAUUACAGGCAUGGGCCACCGCACCCGGCAGUUUUUUAUUUUUAUUUUUAUUUAUUUUUAUUUUUGAGACAGAGUCUUGCUCUGUUGCCCAGGCUGGAGUGCAGUGACGAGAUCUCAGCUCAUUGCAACCUCUGCCUCCCAGGUUCAAGCGAUUCUUCUGUCUCAGCCUCCUGAGUAGCUGGGAUUACAGGCGCAAGCCACCACACCUGGCUAAUUUUUGUAUUUUUAGUAGAGGCUGGGUUUCUUCAUGUUGGUCAAGCUGGUCUCGAACUCCCGGCCUCAGGUGAUCUGUCUGCCUCUCCUCCCAAAGUGUGAGUCAUCCUACCUGGCCUGUUUUUUAUUUUUAAACCAUAAUUUAUUGAUUUUUUUUUUUGAGAUGGAGUCUCGCACUGUCGCCCGGGCUGGAGUGCGAGUGCAGUGGUGUGAUCUCGGCUCACUGCAAGCUCCGCCUUCCAGGCUCAAGCAAUUCUCCUGCCUCAGCCUCCUGAGUAGCUGGGAUUACAGGCGCCCACCACCACGCCGGGCUAAUUUUUUGUAUUUUUAGUAGAAACGGGUUUCAUUAUGUUGGCCAGGCUGGUCUUGAACGCCUGACCUCGUAUCCACCCGCCUCAGCCUCCCAAAGUGCUGGGAUUACAGGCAUGAGCCACCACGCCCAGCCCAUAAUUUAUUGAUUUUUUAAAAUUUGUCCAGCCUUCUAUUACCACGUCGAAUCCAUUAGCUACAGCCAUCCCAUGAGAAGCUGAGUGGAUUCAGCCCCACCUCCUGCUCACAGACCCUGUCCGAGCACCUCAUUUGUCCCAACAGCAUUACUGCAGGACCCCCAGGACGUUGGACUGCCAGCUCCCUGGGUCUCCUCCUCUCUGGGGCAGAUCCUCAGUCCUCCCUUGACUUCACGACUGUGGCCAGAUCAUGUGUGGACUGUCCCUCUCUUUGGGUCUCCAGAGCGCUUGCAUCAAACACCCCUAACUCAGAAGUGUGCAGCCACACUGGGACUCAGAACCCAACAACAGGGACAGAAGACUCACGCCCUUGGGGUGCCCGGUCUCGUGGCAUCAGGCAUGACUUCCAGCUCCUGCGCCUUCCCCAGCAACUGCUGACUGGGGACCCAGACCGGGAGCUGAGCGACGGGCCUGGCGAGCGAAGCUCGGGGUCUCACUCAGGCACCAGCCCCUCCUUGCCCCAGGCUUGAGUGACUCACAGCCCUAUUCAGGCAGGAGCUGCUCUUCUGGGGUAUCGCGAUCCACUUAAGGAUGAGGCAGACUUGGUGACAAGCUGGUCUGAGCAGGUAUGGGAGCCCCCUGGGGAGACGGAAGAAGGGAGGAAGUUGCCUUCUGCCUGGGGAGGGUUUGAGAGGGAGAGGGAAGCCUAGGGCUCCCACCAAGGCUGAUAUUGACAGCCAGGGUUUGGGGCUGAAGCCAGGAACCGUCGCUCUCUCUGGUUCUUACUGGUAGCCCUCAUGGGGGUCCCUGACGCCAGAGCCUCCAAGGCUGCAUGUGCCAGCCCAGGGCUGCCCACAUACCCAUGUAUAUCCCAGAAUAGGCACCAGGGUAGGGAACCCAAACUAGCAUGAGUGACAGAGCAGGUGGUCAGGGAGAAACAGACAUCAAACCCAGCCAGGAGAGAGACACCGCAACAGAGAGACAGAGAAGGGAAACCAGAGACGAGAGGGAAAGUGAGACAGAGACGGACAGAGCCUCAGAGAGGUAGGAAGUGAGCCCGAAGGGAAGGUGACAGGUUGAUAGAGAAAAGCAGGCAGACAGAGCAGAGGAACUCAUGCCUCAGGAUGCAAAAGCCACAUGGACAGGGCGUGGAGCAAGGAGCCGAGCCCUGCAAGGUCAGCGCUUCCAGAGCCAGAACUGAGCCCAGUGAGAGCGCACCCUGGGGCAGCCUGGAUUCCUGGGGUGUCCCCGGCAGCCACACACAGCCAUGCACUACCCAACUGCACUCCUCUUCCUCAUCCUGGCCAAUGGGGCCCAGGCCUUUCGCAUCUGCGCCUUCAAUGCCCAGCGGCUGACACUGGCCAAGGUGGCCAGGGAGCAGGUGAUGGACACCUUAGUUCGGAUACUGGCUCGCUGUGACAUCAUGGUGCUGCAGGAGGUGGUGGACUCUUCCGGCAGCGCCAUCCCGCUCCUGCUUCGAGAACUCAAUCGAUUUGAUGGCUCUGGGCCCUACAGCACCCUGAGCAGCCCCCAGCUGGGGCGCAGCACCUACAUGGAGACGUAUGUGUACUUCUAUCGGUCACACAAAACACAGGUCCUGAGUUCCUACGUGUACAACGAUGAGGAUGACGUCUUUGCCCGGGAGCCAUUUGUGGCCCAGUUCUCUUUGCCCAGCAAUGUCCUUCCCAGCCUGGUGUUGGUCCCGCUGCACACCACUCCUAAGGCCGUAGAGAAGGAGCUGAACGCCCUCUACGAUGUGUUUCUGGAGGUCUCCCAGCACUGGCAGAGCAAGGACGUGAUCCUGCUUGGGGACUUCAAUGCUGACUGCGCUUCACUGACCAAAAAGCGCCUGGACAAGCUGGAGCUGCGGACUGAGCCAGGCUUCCACUGGGUGAUUGCCGAUGGGGAGGACACCACAGUGCGGGCCAGCACCCACUGCACCUAUGACCGCGUCGUGCUGCACGGGGAGCGCUGCCGGAGUCUGCUGCACACUGCGGCUGCCUUUGACUUCCCCACGAGCUUCCAGCUCACCGAGGAGGAGGCCCUCAACAUCAGUGACCACUACCCCGUGGAGGUGGAGCUGAAGCUGAGCCAGGCGCACAGCGUCCAGCCUCUCAGCCUCACUGUUCUGUUGCUGCUAUCACUCCUGUCCCCUCAGCUGUGCCCUGCUGCCUGAGCGUCCCCCUACCCCCCCAGGGCCUGCUGCCUUUUGGGACUUAAACCCCAGCCUCCCCCGUCCAUCCAGCCCUGGGGCUGGGGGGCUUCAACUAUAGUUGCCCUGUGACUGUAGUCCACCCCUGCCUGCCUUGUUUGAUUUGGCUCUUGUUCUUUGGUUGGGCUUGUGCCUAGAUUAGGAGAGGAAGCCAGGGGCCCUGCACUCAUGCCACCUGCCAGGUAGUGUAGUAUCAGGAGUGGAGACAAAGUGGGCUCUGGGUUGGGGUAGGGGAAGGGAGGGUUCAGAAAGAGGAAUGAAGAUGUUGUAUGACAAGAAGGAAAGUUACUGAGAACAAAAACCCAGAUUGGUGAGAUAGGACACUUGUGCAGCAGAUAUGCCAAUGGGCCAUGUUUAUUGUGGAUUGGUAAGAAUCACCAGGAAACCAUUAAGCCCCAAUAGCUACAAGGAGGGUGGUUAAUCUGCUAUAUCAAACUCCUUCCCUGAAACCAGCAAACACCGGGAAACAUUUUGGCUCAUUAUAAUCCGGUGAACAAUGCAGUCAGGCCUGUUAUAACCGCUGAGCAGCCACACUCGCACCUCCUGGGUGCUGUAGUCUGUGUUGGUACAGGCUUCUGCAUGCCUGGUAAAGUCCAGCCAAGGCUGGUCAAGGCAACAUCUCCACACAGAAAAUCUGCACCAGUUAUGUAAGCUAAAAAGCUGUGUGAACCCAGGUGUCCCGGAAAGGGGCUGCAGGACACAGCAAAAUGCCAGCAGCAUGCCGGACCCCUCCCUUCCAUCCUCCUCUCCAAAGAAGAGAGGUCAGGAAAAACACUGGCUGGGACGCUAGAAGGGUCAUGUGUUAACUAUAAUCACAUUUAUGGUUUGGAACCAUCACCCCAAGGUAAAAAAAAAAUAAAAGGUAUUCCCAGGUAUGUUUGGCAAAAUAAAAUAAAGGUAAUUAAAAACCUAAGAAAUGGCUGUAAACUGAGAUUACAAAAAACCAGAGGCCUUUUGGGAGCCACAGGCUGGGGGCUGGGGCCAACAUACCCCAGCUCUGGGACCAAAAGCCUUUGGAGUCCUGUCCCUGGAUACAGAUGCUCAGGCCACCCACCUAGCACUCCUCUCAUUUUUGCUGCUCCCCCAAAAGCCAGCGCUGUUCUACAAUAGUUCAGGUCAGACAUCUAAGAUCCCCAGGCCAAACCAUGCCACACACGUGUCUGUUCCGAGGUCUUGUUACAAAUGACCAAAGGUUAGCCUAGACCUUUGGUCAGGUGGUGAAGGCCCUGGGAAUGCAGGUUCUAGAAGGGGUGGGGGCAUGGGGCCCAGGAGGUUGCUAGAGAUAGGAAAUGGGGCAAAUCGCAGGUGACCUCAGCAGUACCUGGAUGAUUCCCACCAAGGAGGAAUGGCCAAACCAGAUGGGUGAGAACAAGCCCAAUGUGAUGCACACCUACCCUUGCUAAAUAAACGCUGCUGGUCAGCCUCUAGCCCACAA